AGGUGACUUUGCGAAGGCAUGGCGGGGACACUGUGAAUGUCAGCCCAGAAGGUGAUCAGAGCCUGUUAAUUAAAAUGGAAAGAAGACAGAAGGGAAGGUAGACAUCAGGUUCUCCCUGGAGACUUUUCGUUUUCAUUUACGCUGCGGAAACUGACGUUUUUGCCUAACACCCCAUGUAAUGUAAACGUAUAGGCUUGAGUACGUGUCCGGCCGCAUGUGUAGUGAACCCUAAAGCUUUCCUAAUUGUAGUUAGCAUCGUCCCUAAGCGGAACGAUUUUCCGUGAACAUGAUUUGUACUUUUCUACGAGCCGUACAGUAUACGGAGAAGCUGCACAGGUCCUCGGCAAAGCGAUUGCUUUUGCCAUACAUCGUGCUUAACAAAGCGUGCUUGAAGACUGAGCCCAGUUUGAGAUGUGGGCUUCAAUAUCAAAAGAAAACGCUGCGACCUAGAUGUAUUCUUGGAGUCACCCAGAAAACCAUCUGGACGCAGGGACCGAGCCCCCGAAAAGCAAAGGAGGAUGGCAGCAAACAAGUGUCUGUGCACAGGAGUCAGAGAGGGGGAACCGCCGUCCCAACAUCACAAAAAGUGAAAGAAGCCGGAAGAGAUUUUACCUAUUUAAUAGUGGUGCUUUUUGGAAUCAGCAUUACAGGUUGCAAAAAACAGCAAGUGGCUUGUUUUACACGAUUUUCAAAGAACUUUUUUCUUCAUCCAGUCCUAGCAAGAUAUAUGGGAGAGCCUUAGAAAAAUGCAGAUCACAUCCUGAGGUGAUCGGUGUCUUUGGUGAGUCUGUUAAAGGCUAUGGGGAGGUGACAAGGCGGGGUCGCCGGCAGCAUGUCAGGUUCACUGAAUAUGUAAAAGAUGGGCUGAAACACACGUGUGUGAAAUUCUACAUUGAGGGCUCUGAGCCAGGGAAGCAAGGAACGGUGUAUGCGCAAGUGAAAGAGAACCCAGGAAGUGGUGAAUAUGAUUUUCGAUAUAUAUUUGUAGAAAUUGAAUCUUAUCCUAGAAGAACUAUUAUCAUUGAAGAUAAUCGAUCCCAAGAUGAUUAAAAUAGGGUUUCUGAUGGAUGUUGAAUGGCGUGGACUCGCUACUCCGUUCUUCACAGCUGCCUUCCAGAAUGUGUUCAAAAGAAAGACAAGAAGGAGUGUAUGGCUUAUAAAGUGAAUCUAAUACAGUAUUUGUUGCAUUUAAACAAACUAGACAUUUUCUUACGGAAAAAUUAUGAAAUACAGCAUAUUUUAUGUUCUCCCAUUGACUCAAUCAUGACAAUAUUUCUGCUUUAACACCAUCUUUCAUGAUUAGAAAUGUUUGUUAUUGGAAAUGUUACACCAUGUAAAUAAAGGAAAUAGAUUUUAGUAUUGUAUUCAUUUUAUAUUAUAGAACUGCAUAAUGUCUGCAGAAUAAAAUUAAAACUAACAAAUAUGUCAUUAGCAGCUGCCCUCCGCAUACUUUGGAAUCUGACUUGAGAUAAGCAUGUGAAAAUGGUUGAGGGCCAUAGGGAACCAGAUGGUAAAUACAUUCUUCAAAAUUGUGUGAGUUUUAGGAAUCUGUCUCAUAUUUCGCGCUUCAUGAAUUAAGGGCCUAGUACAUAGCGGGAAAAGUACACACUCCCAAGUUGGGUAGACCUGGGCACCCACCCCACCUUUUCUAGCAGGUGCGUGGUCAAGUGUCCCUGUUGUGUGGGUUGUUAGGAUGGCAGUGUGAUGAGAGGUACAAGCCUGGACCAUAGAAGGCAGCCAUGAAGUGCCCUCAUCCCCUUUAGAACUUACUUGCACUGAUACUUCUGACUGCCAAAAGAACAUGGGAGUGAAUGAGAGACAUUCAAAUACGUGUGUGAGGCCCCUUAAAGAAAAAAAAAAAAAAAAAGGAAAUUCUAUUUUAUUUGAAAUAUUUGCUGGGGAUUUGGAAAAAAGUGACCUUCACUUACAAGAUCCUGAUUCCAUAUCUAUGUAAGUGCUAUGUGCAUUGGGAGGGGUCUAGAACCAUGUUUAUCUGCGGUGGCUUCAGUGUGAGGUAUCCCCUCUGAUGUGUUUGUUCCUUCUCCCCGAGAACUGUCUGUAGAGGAAUUUCUGAUGUGUUCUUGAAAUUUUGGGAUAUUCAGGAUAGAGAGACCUCCAGGCAAUCUAUCUCCCCUUUUUACUUUAUCUCCCUGCUUAAUUUAGUUAGUUUCUUGGUUUGACUGCUUGUUUUAGAUGUUUUUAAUUAUAAAAAUUUCCAACAUUUAAGGAGUAUAGAAAAUAUAACAGACACUCGUCUCCCUGACGUAACACACUUUGACUGAAUGAGGCCUUAACUUAGGCUUUCUCUCCUAAUCGUUUUUUCCUUUGCUAUAGAAUGUUCAGUUUCAGGAUUCACUGAAAUGUCAACAUUUAACAGGCUGAGAAGUUCCACUUGCUAUCCUAAACUCAAAAAAGCAGCCCUGCUCUUCAAACAACCUGCUCAAACUGUAGCUUGCUGAAGAAGCCCGGCAUCUGAGCUCAGGUGGGGAUUUAGCCACCCUCCAUGGCCCUGUCAUUUGACUUAAGACUGUUUGCUUUUUCUGUAUUCAUUUUUAUGCACCUGCCAUUUUACAAUAUGCUCAUGCCCCUUUAAGAUCUGAGCUUUUGGCCAGGCGAGGUGGCUCAUGCCUAUAAUCCCAGCACUUUGGGAGGCUGAGGCAGGUCAAUCACUGGAGGUCAGGAGUUCAAGACCAGCCUGGCCAACAUGGUGAAACCCUAUCUACUAAAAAUUCAAAAAAAAAAAAAUUAACCAGGCACGUUGACACACUCCUGUAAUCUCAUCUACUCAGGAGACAGGAGAAGCGCUUGAACCCAGGAGGCAGAGGUUGCAGUGAGCCAAGAUCAUGUCACUGCACUCCAGCAUGAGUGACGGAGUGUGACUUCGUCUCAAAAAAAAAAAACAAAAAACAGAUCUGAGCUUUUAUAAUUAGAAAUAAAACUAAAUUACUUUUUCAAAAGGAAAAACUCUGUACCAAUAAGAGAUUCUUCUGUAUAGCCACAGGAAAAUGUGAUGUGUAACUCUCUAGAUCUCUGUUUUCAUUCCCUCUGAUGUACCCUACUAAAUGUUAAAAUUUCUGUGUUUUAAGACCCUCUUUAAUCCA